AAAUCCGUAUUUUAGAAAUUGAGGAAACUGAGGUUCAGAGAAAUAAAGUAACCUGCCUAUGGUUUCCCAGCCAGUAAGUGGCAGCUCUUCUGAUAGCAAGUCCAAGGUUCUUUCCCCUUUCAGAUCAGGCACUAGAAAGAAUCUUAGGCUGAAAAUAUACUGAGUUGUGCCAGUAACUGGGAAGGAUUGUGUUUGUUUUAUGGAAACAGGUUCUGUCAGCUUCUCUAUAGUCUAUAGUUGUUAAGAUUAAAAUGUGAGACCAGAAGAGCAGCUUUGAAAGAGAAGUAGAAUUCUUUCACAGUUUUGCUGAGGAAGGACAAGUCUGAAGGAACAGGCCUUCUGCUUAUGUAAGACAAACCCAGGAAUCUUUCUGGAUCAGAGGAGUUUUCAGACAAAGGGCAGAGAGAGACUAGAUCCCCAAAAGGGUUCCUAGGUAACACUAGCAGCUUUGGUUAUCCAAGAGGCUGCUGGUGACUGUAGGUAGGGACUUCCUGUGCCUUUUGAAAAGUGUAGGAGAGUAGGAUCAGGGUGUUGGCUCUUUUCUUUGUGAAGACAUAGCCCCAUUAAAAGCAGAUCAAGGUGAGCACAUGGCUGCUGCUUUCCUCCUUUGGUUCUAUCAGUACAAGCUCCUUAGCCACCACCAGCCUCUUUCCUAGAAGCCCAUUACUCACUCUUUCAGUAGCAGCCUACUAAACUAUUGUGUCUUGUUUGUGCUUGUUCAGGAGAACAGAUGAGGUGGACGUGUGGGAGGUGGGGACGUAAUGUUCUCUUUCUGAGUUUGUGUGGAGUUUCCAGGGCUAGGCUCCUCUCUCACAUCAGCCAAAUUGAUGUGACUUGUUUCCUUCUGGCUGCCAUUCCCAACUUUCCAGAGGCUGAGGUGCAUGAUUUCAAAUUGAAGGGGGAGUAGAAUUUGACUUUGAAGGUAGGGGUAAUUCCCUCCAAUCUAAACAUGCACACUCGAGCACACUCUCUGCUCAAUUCCAAGGUGCAUAGUAAUUGCUGGUAUUACAAACAGGUAAUUCCACCCUUGCAAAGGAGGAGGGGACUUAAACAAUGAAAGCCAGACGUCACAGGCCUUUGAGGUUUAUAGUGAAGCAGGCACAUAUGCCAUAAUGACUUGAAGGCUCAAGUGGGACUAGUUUUUAGUGCUACCUACCCCUCCCCAGCAUGUGAUUCAUGCAAAAUGCAGCCACCUUAAUGCAGAUCUUUCUAGACAAAUCUACACUCGUGAUGGGGACGUGUUUAUCAUAUUACAUCGCAGUGUUUCUUCAACAAGAGGAAUGGUUCCUGAACAGGACGUAGCUCAUGUUAAUGAUGAGCAAAGCUCUCUGGGGCAUGAACCCGCUGAUCCCAUCAUCUUGUUCACGGCCAGUCUGUUGGAUGAAUGGUCACUGUAAGCAGCAGGUGCUAAUGAGCUGAGCAAGCAUUCUGUGGCCCACAGCUAGUUUGUGCAGUUGGAGCCCUCCCCAGAUUCUCGUGGAUAAUCCCCAGACACCCCCUUUUCUCUCUUCACAUGGAAAAGCCUCAUGAUCAAAUUUUGGCACCAUCUCUUCAAAGGGAAUCCCCCUGUUGUAGCAGGUUGCAUCGUGGUUGGUAAUCUGUGGUGAAGAGAUUGUUUUCUGAAAGCUGCGUUGGAGGCUGUGACAGAGCUGAGAGCCUGUGUGGAGCGGAUGGGGAGGCUUUCUCAAUAACAUGGCCCUUUGCCAUUAGCCUUGCCAUGACCACAUUUUUCACCAGCGUCCCCCCCUGGAUUCAAGAUGCAAAGCAGGAGGAGGAAGUGGGCUGGAAACUAGUUCCCAGGCCUCGGGGCCGGGAGGCGGAGAGUCAAGUGAAGUGCCAAUGUGAAAUUUCGGGAACACCUUUCUCAAAUGGGGAGAAGCUGAGGCCUCACAGCCUCCCGCAACCAGAGCAGAGACCAUAUAGCUGCCCUCAGCUGCACUGUGGCAAGGCUUUUGCUUCCAAAUACAAGCUGUAUAGGCACAUGGCCACCCACUCAGCCCAGAAACCCCACCAGUGUAUGUACUGUGAUAAGAUGUUUCACCGCAAGGACCAUCUGCGGAACCAUCUGCAGACCCAUGAUCCUAACAAAGAGGCCCUCCACUGCUCUGAGUGCGGUAAGAAUUACAAUACGAAGCUGGGCUACCGGCGCCACCUGGCCAUGCAUGCUGCCAGCAGCGGUGACCUCAGCUGCAAGGUGUGCCUGCAGACCUUUGAGAGUACCCAGGCCCUGCUAGAGCACCUGAAGGCCCACUCACGCCGGGUAGCAGGCGGUGCCAAGGAGAAGAAGCACCCCUGUGACCACUGCGACCGGCGGUUCUAUACUCGUAAGGAUGUACGGCGGCACCUAGUGGUGCACACAGGCCGUAAGGACUUCCUGUGCCAGUACUGUGCCCAGCGGUUUGGCCGUAAGGACCACCUGACGCGUCAUGUCAAGAAGAGCCACUCGCAGGAGCUGCUCAAGAUCAAGACAGAGCCCGUGGACAUGUUAGGCCUACUCAGCUGCAGCUCCACAGUCAGUGUGAAGGAAGAGCUGAGCCCUGUGCUGUGCAUGGCCUCUCGGGACGUAAUGGGGACCAAGGCCUUCCCUGGCAUGUUGCCCAUGGGCAUGUAUGGUGCCCACAUCCCUACCAUGCCCAGCACGGGCGUGCCACACUCCCUGGUGCACAACACGCUGCCCAUGGGUAUGAGCUACCCUCUGGAAUCCUCACCUAUCUCUUCCCCAGCUCAGCUCCCUCCAAAAUACCAGCUUGGAUCUACCUCAUACUUGCCCGACAAAUUGCCCAAAGUGGAGGUGGAUAGUUUUCUGGCGGAGCUUCCUGGAAGCCUGUCUCUCUCAUCCGCUGAACCCCAGCCCGCCUCACCUCAGCCGGCGGCAGCUGCGGCCCUCCUAGAUGAAGCACUGCUUGCCAAGAGCCCCGCCAACCUCUCUGAGGCCCUCUGCGCUGCUAAUGUGGACUUCUCCCACCUACUGGGCUUUCUUCCACUCAACCUGCCCCCGUGUAACCCACCUGGGGCCACAGGAGGCCUGGUCAUGGGCUACUCCCAGGCUGAGGCACAGCCCCUGCUUACCACUUUGCAAGCUCAGCCUCAAGAUUCCCCAGGAGCUGGGGGACCACUGAACUUUGGGCCUCUGCACUCCUUGCCUCCUGUCUUCACGUCUGGCCUGAGUAGCACCACCCUGCCUCGUUUCCAUCAAGCAUUCCAGUAGCCCCCACAGAGGCCCUCAGCUCAGUUUUUGGCUCUGUUAUGGAGCCUUAGUACCCACCCCGUCUGUGUCCCCCAUGAAGGCAGCUGAGCUUUCAGAGCUGGGUUCAAAAAAAAAAAUUCCAGUGUCUGUAUACAGGAGCACUUGGUUUGGGGGUUCAGGCUCUAGGAUCGAUUCCAGAAGGAGCCUUGAGCCCCAACCCCGUGAAAAGAUCUCAUACCGUAGGACUUCAGGUAUUAUUUACUUUUAUUUUUUUGACCUGAAUCGGGAGCCACACUUGGCCCUCUUCCUCUCCAAAGCGCCAGAACCUCCUUCUCUUUGGAGAAUGGGGAGGCCUCUUGGAGACACAGAGGGUUUCACCUUGGAUGACCUCUAGAGAAAUUGCCCAAGAAGCCCACCUUCUGGUCCCAACCUGCAGACCCCACAGCAGUCAGUUGGUCAGGCCCUGCUGUAGAAGGUCACUUGGCUCCAUUGCCUGCUUCCAACCAAUGGGCAGGAGAGAAGGCCUUUAUUUCUCGCCCACCCAUUCCUCCUGUACCAGCACCUCCGUUUUCAGUCAGUGUUGUCCAGCAACGGUACCGUUUACACAGUCACCUCAGACACACCAUUUCACCUCCCUUGCCAAGCUGUUAGCCUUAGAGUGAUUGCAGUGAACACUGUUUACACACCGUGAAUCCAUUCCCAUCAGUCCAUUCCAGUUGGCACCAGCCUGAACCAUUUGGUACCUGGUGUUAACUGGAGUCCUGUUUACAAGGUGGAGUCGGGGCUUGCUGACUUCUCUUCAUUUGAGGUCACAUUUUUCCCCCGUGGGGAAAUAAACUGACUUUGGACUGCUUCAGUCUCUGCCAUCUUCCAUGACUGCAUUUGUUCCUGCCUGCCUCGGCGGUAUCCACAGAAGACAGGCAAGAGGAUUGGAGCAGUUUUCUCACAGGUCUGCAAUUCUGUUUUUCUCCAAGUACAUUAUGACCCCCUCAUCCUUCUCUUGAACUGGAGAGGGGAAGAAAUGAAAGGCAUGCCCACGUCCGUCACCUCCCCAUCCCCUAGUCCCCACCUUGAACAUCAUGAGCUGUUGUUAUUAGUCUUGGAAGCAGAGUCUGGGUUGGUGUGGAUAGCAAAGGAGGAAGUCUGAGCCCCUCAUUGGUCUUCCUCCCACCUGUCCCUUUUCCGGGAAGUUGUGGAAUUGUUGGAAGAAGAGUUUGCAGAAGGUUAGGAAUGGGUAGAUAGCUAAGUCCUAAUCUAUGGGUACAUUGUUGUGUCCCAAACCAAAAUUUUCCUUAUCCACAAUGUCCCUUCUGUCUCUUCCACUUUACAGUGGACUCGGCCACUGUGCAUAGGCUUCUCUGCUCUCCAUCAAAUCACUUCCACUUUCCUGUGCCCCCACCCCCGCCUCCAGUUUUCCGCUAGUAUCCGGCAAGGUUUCUUGCAACAAAUGAUUAGUUCUUUUCUUCUGACUCGUGGGGCUCCCUGCUGCAGAGAGCACAGCCCUUGCCUGGAGCCCAGGAACCCCAUCCUUGCUUCAUCUCAGUUCUUCAUGGGCUUCACUCUUCCCACUCACGGAAGGGAGGUAGCUCAGGGACCUCCACUGUGGGACCCUUGAGACGCUUCCACUCUGAUUCAGAAACACACUUCUACCUCUUUACUGUUAACUCUUAACAGAUGCAGUCAGCAGUUUCUGGGCACUUCUCUCAGUAGGUGCCUCAUGCUGACUUCUCCAGUAGGGUUUCAGGACAAACUACCAAGGAAUUGCCUCAGCCUCCUACCAGUCCUCCCUCACCCACCUUCUGUCUAGGUUCACUUGGUUUGUCAUCAGGAACUGAGCAGGUCCAGGACUCAGCUUUCUGCUUCAGCCUAAGCCAGUACUCCUUGUUUGAGGUAAAAGCCUUAAAAUUUAGCUCCCUAGCUCUUGAUUAGAAGCAAUUUGGAGUAAGUGUGUUUUGAUUUAGGCAGGGUAGCUUGGGAUACCUUUUUAAAAACACCAGAUAUUAAAAUGUCUGGCAAGGUUAGAAUCAGACUAGAUGAUUUGCUUCUAAAAAUUAGUUUCAGUGAGUCCCAGGGACUAAUUAAGGUUUAUUUUAAAAAGUGUCUACCUUGGUACGCAGCCACCUCCUGCAUGCUGUGCAUGUUAUUGGGACUUGUAUUAUAGGUGAUGGUAUGUGAGAAUCCAGUUGGGACUCGCUGUUGCCAUCCUCUUUGUUGUAUCUGGUUUUCAUCACUAGACUCAGCAACCCUUCUCACCUUAACUGCCACCUUCCCUACACUCUCAGUUUACAGAGGCCACUGGGCCUCUGGCUGCAGAAUACAAAGUCCCGGGCUGUUAGAGGAGUCCUUUCCUCUCUGCCUGCCCUUUCCUGUCCCUCCCUCGAAUUCUCUCUCCCCGUAAGUGAUGCUGGAAAAGUCAUAGGACUGGCAAAGCAACUGUUUAAACCCUUUGUAACCGGGGCCUUGCCCCCACCUCCUGUCUUUUCUCCUUGCCUUCCCCACUCCUGUGUCCUCCCAUCUAUCCUGUCUUUCCUUUCCUCCUCUCAGUGUCCUCAGCACCCACAAGGAAUUUUCCUAUCACUGUGAACUUUGCUGGUACAGAGGAAUAAUAUCUGCCUUCACCUUUUUUUUUUUGGACCAUAGCUAGCCAGUCAUUUCUUAAACCUCCCUUCCUAAAAUCUGGGGGGUCGGGGGGAAAGAAAAAAAAAGCCUUAGUGGCCUGGUUGUUCAAAGGAUAAGAAUAGCUUUAUCCUGCACUCAGUACCCGAACUCACUUCAGUAUGCUUACUGAGGCCAUGAGAACCUGAGGGGCAUCUGCCCAGGACAGGAGCCAUGGCAUAUGACAAAGACCAAUGAGGGACCAGGAAAAAAAGUGAUGUCCCCUUUCCCUGCCACCUCCAGCCUCUGCCAGCAAUGAGCUGUCCCCCUCCCACCCUACACAGUAGCUGGUCAGGGCUGAGUACAGUCCUGGGGGUAAGGGGAUGACAUGCCCAGGUGUCAGCUCAAAGGAUCUCUGCAUCAUCUUGAGGUGGGAGGCAGGGAAAGGAGCGCCAAUGAGGUUCCCUGCAACCCCCGCCCUCCAGCCCACCGCCCAACCUUUUACAAAUGGCAUUUUCUUAAUUGAAAAUCCGGGAAGCAGGUGUGAUUACUUUUUUGCUCGUAGAUAUUGUCCUAAGUUGGAAUUCUCCCACUGCCCUAAAACUUUCCCUAGUAGUCCUUUAAACUCCCCCCUCCCUUUUUGGUAGCUGUUUUCUCCGUCCUCUCUCCACCUGCCCUCUUAUCUAGGAGCUGUUUGUAAGCACGAUUUUUUUAACAGGUUAUAUUGUACAGGAUCAAUAUUUUGCUUUUUAACAAGGAUAUUUAUGUAAUAAGAAACUUUGCCUUAGGCAGGUGUUGGCCAGAAAAGUCCAGAUUCCUCUGGGAUCCCACCCUGGCCUCUCCUGGAACUCUGAACCUGCUGUGGAAGGAAUUGGCCAUGACCUUCACCUCUGGAGAGUAGGGUCUAUGGCGAGGGAAAAGGGUGUUCACCAUGAUAACCUAGUGCCUCCAUAGAGGGGUUUGGAAAAAUUCCAGUCCGAUUUCUUUGUGUGUCAGCUGACUUCCUUAGCUGAUUGUUCCCACUUGCACCUCUCCACCUUUGGCACUAGAACUCCUGAGACACCACUUCUCAUGCUUCUCCCUCCCUACCAGCGGUCAAGGCUUUGGAGCCACUCUUUUGUAACUCCAGAUUAUUUAAAGAGAAAAGUACAAGACAGAAAUCUUCUAGCACUUUGUAAACACAGUGAAUAACCUCUUGGAGUAUUUUUGGCUUUAUAUAAAACAAGGUUUUUAAUUGUAAAGUAUAAGUGCCAUUAGAAAAUGCACAGGGCAUAUCUUUGUUAAAGUAGAUUUUUCAAUGUUUUACAGAAUUACAUUUUCAAAAAAAGGUUUUUAUAAUGAAGUUGUUUAUUAAAAACUUCUGAAUGAUGUGUU